ACGCCUCAGGCAGCGGAGGACCCUGACUCUGGGCGCUGCUGACCCGGGCAAGGCCCCACUGUGAUUCGUGCCAUGACCUCAGAAUGUCACUGGUGCUUAGCACCUAUCUGCUCUCUGGCCUGCCUCAGUGGUCUACAGCAGUUACACACAGGCAGUGGUAUCUGUGAGCAGCUCUGUGGACUCAAAGGUUUUCUCCCUGAGAGGCAUGACCCAGGCCAGCUGAUUCAUCAGAAUCAGGUGAGCGUGACCUGCUCUCUUCCCUCCAGGCGGACUUGGGGACAGUGGCUACGGUGCGGGCGGUGUUGGCCUCUGUGGGGCAGCUACCGAGGAGGGUCAUCCCUGAGCACUCACCAGGCGCCCGUUCUACACUGCCCGUGUAGACGAUUGGCUCUUUCGUCUCCAUGGUGGCUUCGUAGAGUGGGUGCUGUUCCCAAAUGUCCCCAUUCGACAGAUGAGACGUCUGGGGUCAGAGAGGCAGUAACCGGCCUGGGAAUCCGGACAUGACCCUGAGUUUUGCUCUCAGCCCUGCCGUGUGCUGUGCUGGAAUUCAGGCCUGAACCCUGUGACCUCCCUGCCCUAGAUCCCAAAUCUGCCCAGGUUUCCCAUCCCGAUGGGGCAGAGCCUGGUCCUGGCAGAGCCACUGGUAUAGAGCCACUGGUACAGAUCCACUGACGGUCCUCAGAACACCUCUGUGCCCUAAGCUGGGUCCUGAUGGUCGCUGUGGGCCCCACUGAACACACAUGGUCCCUUGUCCGGGGGAGCCUGCUGCCCUUGGGCAGCUGUGGAAAAUGAAGGAGCCCUGGAGGGCUGGCUGAGGGGAGACUAUCUUCCCUUGUGUUCAAAGGGGUCCGGGCACUAGGGUUCUCCCCAGGUAUUUCUUGCUCUGCGUGGUCCUCUUGAGGCCUCGCCCUCCUUUUGCCUCGAGUAUUCCCAGGAGGGACGGUCCAUCCAGCUGUUCUCCAGGACCAAGGACCCACUGUUCUUCCUCAGUGACCCAGGAAAAUGAAGCCUCCUCCUGUUGGGACGGCUCAGAAUGGUGGACUCCACAGUCCCUCCGCGAGAGACGUGGUUUCCAUGCGUACAAUAGAUCUUCCUCAUCCCCCAAACCCAACACCCUCCUGCUCAACAGGCGUUAUUCCUAAAGUGGCUUCACUGUUCAGACUGAAGAGCCACGGUAGCCAAAGUGAUGAGCGGAGUAGAACCGAGCAGUCGGGAGAGAUCUUGUUCCCUGUAGGAAACUGGGCAUCGCUGAGGCCCUGAGCAUCCCAGGAGGCCGAUUGCACAGAGACCUCUGGUCGCUGACCCCAGUCUGCCUCCACAUCCCUGGAAUAGCCCAUCAUGGGCCCUUCACCCUUGGCAGGUGGAAACCAUUCAACCUGCUGGGGCCGGUGUGUCCCCAUUUCAUGGCAUUGGGGGACAACAGGAUUCUCUGUCUAGGUCCCACUGUACUCAAGUCCUUGGGAAGAUGCCCACCCCUGCUUGGGACUUGAGACUCCAGAGACUGGAGCAGCUGUGGGCCACUGGGUCUGGCCCCUUUUUCCCUGGGGGCGGCGGUGGAAUGGGGGUUACGCAGCCAGCCAGCAUCUGGGAGCCCGGCGAGAGCGGUUCAGGUGUUCUCCGAAGCCGCCGCGUACAGUGUGACCUUUAGACAAUUCUGUCUCACAGGAUGGACGUGGUAGAGGUCGCGGGCAGUUGGUGGGCACAAGAGCGAGAGGACAUCAUUAUGAAAUACGAAAAGGGACACCGAGCUGGGCUGCCAGAGGACAAGGGGCCUAAGCCUUUUCGAAGCUACAACAACAACGUCGAUCAUUUGGGGAUUGUACAGUCCUGCCCCUCCUGGGAGUCAGCCCCACAGGAAGGCCCUUGUCCUCCCUUCCCUGUGCCUUCUCCUGGGCUGAGCCCUGAGCUGGAAAGGGACAGAGCCAGUCCUUUCUGGGGGUCGGCACCCAGGCUGGGGCCGCUCCAGGCCCCGUGCAGUUCCUCAGCUCUGCCUGGGUUGCCUUACAGUGAGACGGAGCUGCCUCCUCUGACUGCGCGGGAGGCGAAGCAAAUUCGGCGGGAGAUCAGCCGAAAGAGCAAGUGGGUGGAUAUGCUGGGAGACUGGGAGAAAUACAAAAGCAGCAGAAAGCUCAUAGAUCGAGCGUACAAGGGAAUGCCCAUGAACAUCCGGGGCCCGAUGUGGUCAGUCCUCCUGAACACUGAGGAAAUGAAGUUGAAAAACCCCGGAAGAUACCAGAUCAUGAAGGAGAAGGGCAAGAGGUCAUCUGAGCACAUCCAGCGCAUCGACCGGGACGUAAGCGGGACAUUAAGGAAGCAUAUAUUCUUCAGGGAUCGAUACGGAACCAAGCAGCGGGAACUACUCCACAUCCUCCUGGCAUAUGAGGAGUAUAACCCGGAGGUGGGCUACUGCAGGGACCUGAGCCACAUCGCCGCCUUGUUCCUCCUCUAUCUUCCUGAGGAGGAUGCAUUCUGGGCACUGGUGCAGCUGCUGGCCAGUGAGAGGCACUCCCUGCAGGGAUUUCACAGCCCAAAUGGCGGGACCGUCCAGGGGCUCCAAGACCAACAGGAGCAUGUGGUAGCCACGUCACAACCCAAGACCAUGGGGCAUCAGGACAAGAAAGAUCUAUGUGGGCAGUGUUCCCCGUUAGGCUGCCUCAUCCGGAUAUUGAUUGACGGGAUCUCUCUCGGGCUCACCCUGCGCCUGUGGGACGUGUAUCUGGUAGAAGGCGAACAGGCGUUGAUGCCGAUAACAAGAAUCGCCUUUAAGGUUCAGCAGAAGCGCCUCACGAAGACGUCCAGGUGUGGCCCGUGGGCACGUUUUUGCAACCGGUUCGUUGAUACCUGGGCCAGGGAUGAGGACACUGUGCUCAAGCAUCUUAGGGCCUCUAUGAAGAAACUAACAAGAAAGCAGGGGGACCUGCCACCCCCAGCCAAACCCGAGCAAGGGUCGUCGGCAUCCAGGCCUGUGCCGGCUUCACGUGGCGGGAAGACCCUCUGCAAGGGGGACAGGCAGGCCCCUCCAGGCCCACCAGCCCGGUUCCCGCGGCCCAUUUGGUCAGCUUCCCCGCCACGGGCACCUCGUUCUUCCACACCCUGUCCUGGUGGGGCUGUCCGGGAAGACACCUACCCUGUGGGCACUCAGGGUGUGCCCAGCCCGGCCCUGGCUCAGGGAGGACCUCAGGGUUCCUGGAGAUUCCUGCAGUGGAACUCCAUGCCCCGCCUCCCAACGGACCUGGACGUAGAGGGCCCUUGGUUCCGCCAUUAUGAUUUCAGACAGAGCUGCUGGGUCCGUGCCAUAUCCCAGGAGGACCAGCUGGCCCCCUGCUGGCAGGCUGAACACCCUGCGGAGCGGGUGAGAUCGGCUUUCGCUGCACCCAGCACUGAUUCCGACCAGGGCACCCCCUUCAGAGCUAGGGACGAACAGCCGUGUGCUCCCACCUCAGGGCCUUGCCUCUGCGGCCUCCACUUGGAAAGUUCUCAGUUCCCUCCAGGCUUCUAGAAGCAUCUGGGCCAGGGCUCAUGGCUGGAUAAUUUCCCUAGGCUUAACAACCCAAGCAAGCUUCGCAUCCUCGUUUUAUUUUUGGUUAAACUUAUGAAAAUGUAUUAAGAAAGAGUGCAGCUCGAGAGAGAUUCAGAGAUGGAACACACCAGACCCCAGAUCACAAAGCCAACCAUGCCCAGCCCCUCCCAGCACCCCCAGCCCCACGACCAUCGUUCUGAAUUCUGACGACACCGUGAGCCUGCCUUUGUACUUCAAACUCAUGGAAGGAUAACCACCUUCAUGUUUUGAAAUAAAUGUUUCCUGUUGAAAUGA